AGACGCUCGGAGGGAGCCCGGCCGGCUCGGACUGGGCGGCCGGGAGGGAGGGCGCCCCGGGUCACGACGGCGCCCGCAAGCCGAGCGCGGCCGGGACGUGCACCAUGGACCCAAAGGCGGGCGGCGGCGGCGAGGAGGACGACUGCGUGGACUCGGGCGCCGAGACCGGAGGGUCCGACUACAGCCACCUGUCCUCCACGAGCAAUGGAUUCUCCACCUGGCGGAUGCCAUGUUGCCUGUUCCUUUACUGUACACACGGUGACAAAGAAAAGGGAAGAUGGAGCCUCCAGGUUGAACAUACCUGGCCCUCAGGUGAGCUUUCCGUUGAAGAGGCGCAGGACCCUUUCCUGGUCAGCAUCCACAUAAUCGCAGACCCAGGGGAGUCCCAGCCCCUGCAGGAGGCCAUCGACAACGUCCUGGCGUGGAUCCACCCCGACCUCCCGCUGUUCCGGGUGUCCGAGAGGCGGGCGUCCCGGCGGCGGCGGAAGCCCCCCAAGGGCGCUCAGCCAGCGCUGGCUGUGGUGCUGUUCCUGCAGGAGGAGUACGGCGAAGAGCAGAUCCUGCAGCUGCACCGCACACUGCAGCAGCCGCCCUGGCGCCACCACCACACCGAGCAGGUGCACGGCCGGUUCCUGCCCUACCUGCCCUGCAGCCAGGACUUCUUCACGCUGGCCCCUGGGACGCCGCUUUGGGCCAUCCGGCCCGUGCACUACGGCAAGGAAAUCGUGCGCUUCACCGUCUACUGUCGCUACGACAACUAUGCUGACAGCCUCAGGUUCUACCAGCUGAUUCUCCGGAGGAGCCCCAGCCAGAAGAAAGCGGACUUCUGCAUCUUCCCUAUUUUUUCCAACCUGGAUGUGGACAUCCAGUUCUCCCUGAAAAGACUGCCCUGUGACCAGUGCCCGGUGCCCACCGACUCCUCCGUGCUGGAGUUCCGAGUGAGGGACAUAGGCGAGCUCGUGCCUCUCCUGCCCAACCCUUGCAGCCCCAUCAGCGAGGGGCGCUGGCAGACGGAGGACCAUGAUGGGAACAAGAUCCUCCUACAGGAUGGACCCCUGAGUUGCCUCCACCUCUUGGCUACUGUGAAUAACACCGCUAUGAACGUGGGCACAAAGGGUGCAUAAGAAGUUUCCUAAACCUGGCAGAGUACAUCAUGCCUCCGAGAAGAAACGUCAUUCCACUCCUUUGCCGAGCACUGCUGUACCAAGCCAUACACCUGGCAGCAGCCAGCAGUCCCCGCUCAACAGUCCUCACCCGGGGCCCAUCCGGACAGGCCUGCCUCCUGGGCACCAGCAGGAAUUUGCCGGACGAGCCAACAGCACCCCCAACCCUCCCUGGUCUUUCCAGAGAAGCAAGUCCUUGUUUUGUUUGCCCACGGGAGGCCCCUCCCUGGCCUCCUCAGCUGAACCACAGUGGUUUUCAAACACAGGUGCCCCAGGGCACAGGGCAUCAGAGUGGAGGCAUGGCCACCUCCUCUCCAUCGAUGACCUAGAGGGGGCCCAGGAGACAGACGUGGACACAGGCCUGCGGCUGUCCUCAUCGGACCUGUCUGUGGUCUCUGCAUAUUCUGCACCCAGUAGGUUCUGCAGCACAGUGGAGACACCCCUCCCCUCCGAAAGAUGCAGCAGCCACUGGGCAGCUCACAAGGAUUCCAGGGAGGGACCACUGCCCACUGUCAGCAGGGUGACCACAGAGGCCUCCUGGGCUUCCCUCCCUUUCUUCACCAAAAGGUCUUCCAGCUCCUCAGCGACAGCUCGUGCUGCUCCCCCAGCUCCCAGCACCUCCACCCUCACAGACUCCUCCCCACAGCUCCCAUGCGAUACCCCCAAAGUCAAGCAGACUGAUGGAGACAUGCCACCACCCCCAGGGUCGGCUGGCCCCGGGGAUAACGACAUGGAGGAAUUCUACAUCUGAAUGCCCUCUGCUCUUGUUCUCGAAACACACAAACUCAGAGACACAGACUCAGGCCCCACUGCCCCUCUGGCCACUGAGCACACCACAUUCUUCAUGAUCCAUUUCCCAGGAGCCCGUAGCACAUUUGCCUACCACCCACUCUUAGCUGGGGGGUGGUAUAUCUCUAGAGACACAGCAGAAAAAUACUGGCAUUUUUAUGCAAAUAAAUUCUCAACAAACUUGUCAUAAAAUAUAUUUUUUGAAUAUUCAGCAUUUGAGGUAUGGUUUAGUGGGUUUAUACAAUUUAAAUGGCUUAUAUAAUUAUUUGAAAUGAAAAGAAAACCUAGUCAGCCAGAACCAAUUUGGCAAUUUUUCCAUGGUAUGAAGGCAAAUCAAUUAAGGCCAAAACGUUGAAUGUGGGAGAGAUAGUAAGUGACUUGUAUGAGGGAUUACUGCAUAAUAACGUAACGCACACCUUACUGGAUUCUCCAUAUAUAUUUACAUUACCAGAGAACAGUGGCCCUAGGGAUGUUUAAGCACUGCUUAUAAUGGAAAAAGUCAGCUUGAGAAGUAAACGUAUAUCAGACUACAGGUAAUUCCUCAUCUUGAAGCCAUGCAACACCUGCAAAUCUGGAUUUAUACAAAAGUUGCUAAUGUGUUUCAUAAAGAUUUAGCAUGAGUAACAGACUCUUGGUGCAUUUAAAAUAUGUGAGUUCCAGAAAGUAGAUUUGCAUACACCUUUUCAACAGCACAUUUCACUGGAAUGGAUGAGGGGCUUCUGAAGACCACUCCACUACCUGAAUUUAUUUGGAUCACUGAGGAAGAGCAUUUGUUGGGAUUACAGAAUUAUAGGCCAUUAGACAUCAUGGGUAGGUAGUCUUAAGAUCCUUCAACUUUCAAAAACCACAGUCUAAGGACUAUAUUCAAAUGACAAGAGCCGCACUGUAUACUGCUUUCUGCAGUGACCAUGCUGGGUCACGCAUCCUAUGUUUCUCAUUUUUAAAUGAUUUGGAACAUUUUAGCCAGCAUUUUGAUCACACAGAUUAAUAAUGCUGUUCUCCCCAAAACGGGAAACUUUACCUGAAACGCUCUCCUGAACAAACACCAGUGCACUGCCAGCCUCACAUGAUUGCAUGGGAGCUUUAAUUAACGCUGGAGCCCAGCAACCUUGGCUUUUCCUGCCUGUUAUCUGCUACUGUCACACCGUGAAUGGUAUUUGAAUCUCACCUCCCUCUCACCUCAGUAAGAGUAUGUUUGUUUACAGCCCCAACCUCAGCAAUGCCAAAGGCUGGCAUCGGGGGCAGUGCCAAGCUGUCCCUGGAUACUAUUUACCUUUGAGGAAGAACAGCAUGGGUUUGCCAAGCUCAAUUCCCAGGCUGGUGCUCCUUGAAUUAAUCAUGGCACAGUGUUCAUCUCUCUGGAAAUGCCCACGCCAGCCCAGACACAGCCUCAGAGUCCUUUCCAACACGACCCUCCAGGCAGCAGUUACCAACCAUCAGUCUUCAGCUGAAGCUUCAAGUCUUUGCCAUCCUUGUAAUGACAGCCUUAGGCCUUGCCCCAAGCAUUCUGGACUCUCUAACACUCAGAAUUGUAAUGUAAUAUUCUGCUCUAAUUUAAAUUUUUAAAAAUAUAGUCUCCUAAUUCAGGAUAAGGAGUAAGCAAACUUUCUGAAAAGGGCUAGAUAAUAAGUAUUUUAGGCUUUGCCAGUCAUAUGGUCUCUUGCAGCUACUCAACUCUGCCACUGUAGUAUGAAAGCAGCCAUGAGUAAUAUGUUAAUGAAUGGGAAUGGCUGAGUUCCAAUAAAGCUUUAUUUUUUUUUUAUUUGAGACGGGGUCUUGCUCUGUUGCCCAGGCUGGAGUGCAAUGGCGCAAUCUCAGCUCACUGCAAGCUCUGCCUCCUGGGUUCAAGCCAUUCUCCUGCCUCAGCCUCCCAAGUAGCUGCGACUACAGGUGCGCACCACAAUGCCUGGCUAAUUUUUUGUAUUUUUAGUAGAGACAGAGUUUCACCAUGUUGGCCAGGUUGGUCUCAAACUCCUGACUUCGUGAUCCACCCACCUUGGCCUCCCAAAGCACUGGGAUUACAGGCAUGAGCCACCAUUCCCAGCCAAUAAAACUUUAUUUACAAGAACAGCUGGUGGGCCAGAUUUGGCCCAAGGGUCAUAGUUUAUUAUCCCUUGAGCUAGGCUGCUGCCUGAGGUUGAUUCAACAUCCCAGCUCCAGUCAACAACAAAAAUUCUAAGUCUCCCGCCUAAUGCUGCUGUGGUGUGUCAUGCCAAAAAAGUGGGCUACUCAGGUUAGACCAAUGACUUCAGAACCACAGGGCUCAGAACAGGAAGGAGCUUCUUUCUGCAGAGCUGAUUCCUGGAAAGCCACCAGCACUCCACCUUCUGCCCAGAAAUGUGAUUCAGUCAAUAGCUGAUGAGGAAAAGCAACCUGCAAACAUUAGGAAGAAGGAGAAAAAUAAUUCAGAGGUGAUGAUACCACCUCCAAUGAACAGGGAAGCAAGUUCAUCAGUAACAAAAGUCAGUGAGGCAAAAAAAAAAAAAAAAAAAAAAAAAAAAGGCUAAUGGCCGAGGGCUGGCUCCUUCUUUCUCCCUAAUCAGUGUCCUUAUUUCAGUGUGCUCACAUGCUCGCCUAGGACUGCUUUAGAGUACAACUCUGGACCCGCCCUCAUCACAGUCCAAUCUACCAAACUGAGUGACCCUAAAGGACAUCAUAGACAACAUUUGAAAGCAAGAAAUGCAAAAUGUUCCCAUAGCAUCAGGUGAGCAGGGAGAGGAUGCCCACUGUAGACCACAUGGAAAUGGCAGUCCCUCCACGGAGAGGGAAUCACAGGAACACAUUUACCAAAGCCUUCCCUUCCAUUCCUGGCCAUUCCAGUAGCAUCUUCCUCAUCCAGAAGGGCUUCCAAUACUCUCUGGAGGAUCCUGACUCGUUUGGAGUAUUAUCCUUGUAAAAGAUGCUGGCACAUUGUAGGUGCUCAAUAAAUGUGUUCAAUUGAAAAA